CCACACCUGCCCUGGAGGGUGCUGGAGCUCUGAGAUCCCCUGUGUGUGCCCCUAAGAUCUCCAGGCUGUGCAUGGUGUGGCCAACUGGGUCACUGGAGCCUACAAUCAGCCCUUGAGCUGUGUUUAUUUUCAUUCUUUGAGUAGAAAUUCAGGUCUGGUUAGGAGACGUGGUUUUGGUGACUUUUUUUAAUGAGGGUGAUAGGUUGAUAGAAUCAACCCAGAAUCAACCCUGUCCCUUGACUUUCCUGUCUGAGCAGAUGACCAGACCCAGAACCCCAUUAGAAGUAGGGAAACACGUUGUAUCUGUUUUCCGUUGCCAUGACAUUUGGCCGGUGGGAGGGGGAAGUAGUGAGCAUGUGAUAGUUGAGGCUCUGAUGGUCUCCGGUGCCUGAGUUUGUGACCUUGAGGUGGUGUUGGCCUAGGGGUAGUAAUGUGCUGUAUUGCUGGCAAACAGGGCAGCAGGGAAAGGUUGACAAGCAAGAGAGGAACUGAUGACCUCAGCAGGGUGGAGGAACCAGUCCCAAACACCACCUUCUCCAUUAGAAUCCAAGAGGGGGGCCCCGAGGAACUCGGAAAAGAGCACGAGCUCUUUCUCGUGCAUAAACAACAUAGCUCGCGAUGCUGCCACAUUUUAAAUUCUUUAUGUUAUUGUGGUAAGAACACUUAAUGCCCAUACACUGUACUUGCACAUAAAUGUUAAAAAUAGGUGGUCAUCCUUCCCAUGUAGACAAGCCUGACUGUGGAGGAUGGAUAGAGUUGGAGUUAUCUGUUAUGCUGACAUUUGAAAAACAAAUAAAGGCCAGAGUUUAUUUUUUAUAGCCACACACCUUCCCCUGUCACCUCUGGCCUGCUCGAGGGGCCAUUCACAGUGAAGGGGGAGCUUCGUUGCGACUCACUGCCUUGCAGAUUCUGUGCUUCUCUGAAUUGUGUUCAGAAGCCACUUCAGUGUGGACACCUAUACACCCUGCCACACCAAAUUUUUGUGUGUAGUUGUGAGUUCCCCGAACGUCACUGAUGAAAAAGGCAAAAGGACUGUGGUGUGGCUGAGUGUGUGGGGUGGGGACUGACAUGAAGCCGGCUAGAGAAUUAUUCUCUCCAGAAUUCUGCUCUGGGGCGAAGCUGUCCCUGCUCAUUCCAGGAGCAGGGUCUGAGGACAGUGGGCUACCCAGGCCUGCUCUCCAGCCUCGAGCAGAAGGGAGAAAGGAUGAGGAGGAUGGGGUGGCCUAUUUCAUAGACUUCACCGAGCCAACCCUGUACCCCUUUUAACACCUCCAAAUACUCCUGUGUGCAGUUUCAGCGUCCCCCUCUCAGGAGCAGAUGUGACUUAGUGUAUUUCUGAGCUAUGCAGUAGGAAGAGGUCUGUCAUGAGCUGCCUCUUUCCUCAUCAUAGAUGGACUCCCCCUCCUCCCAUCCCACAGGUCUCUGACUCUCACAGCAUCCCAGUUCUCUGCCUUUAGCCAGGACGGGCAGUAAGAGGAGAGGUAGUUUCUAACCCAUCCAUUGAAGAGCAAGCCUAUCUCCAAACCCAUGUGACACUAUGAGGCACAAAUUCCACAGCUGGCUCGGCUGGGCCAGCCUGACUUUAUCUCUCACAGCACAACCACCUCCUGUGGUUGGUCCUUUAUUUAAAAAAAAAAAGUUCUGAGAUUUUAUCAAUUAUUGGGUAAUAUGGACAAUCUACCAGCUUCAUAGGAAACCAAAAUUUGGGCUUUUAAGACUUAAAAACAGAAAGGUAAUCUUUAGUGUCUUCAUCGUUUUGAAGACACAAUGAUUGCAUUUUGAGGCCUGAAAGUUUUUAUGCAUAAUUGGUUGAUUAAGAGGGAAAAACAACACACCCUUUAAAAUGGGCUUGUAGAAUAUGUGGUAUUUGAUGUAAUAGUGCCUUAAGCCCCAAAAGUAUGGGCUGCAGACUGUUUAUACCUUACACUGACCCACAGGCUUACACACAGGCCCACAUAGACAGAAAACUUUAAGAUUAUUGUGGAAAAAAGAGUCUUUAGUACCAAGUAUUUGAUGUUAUAACCAAGGUGACAUUUCCUGAUAGAAUAAGUUUUUCAGGAAAUAUAUGGAAUAAUUUUUCAAAUUUUAUCACCAAGUGUGAUAACAACUGAUGAAAGUUUACCUGGUGGUUUUUAAGAUAAAAUGAUGUCUAACUGGUCAUAUUCUAGUUGUCCUGCUAUGAAGCAGGACAUGCCAGGUAGAGUGUGAUAAACUGGCAAGGCCAAUGAGUCAUUUUGCUCCUUGGUGAUGCGGGAAGGGAAGAUGGGGAGGGAACACAGAUCUGGUGGCAAAUGAACAAAUACAUGCCCCACAGCUCCGGAGGGAGGCCUCAGGCAGGCUUAUCACCUCUUAGAAUCUGUGUCCUGAGAGGGUUUUGGCUCAGAGGGUUUUGGGGGGAUGAGAUGAGAUUGGGUAGAUCAGCACCUCUCCUUCCCAGCAGGACCAGCGGCUUCUUUUCACCCCUCGAACAGCCAGGCCCCCCUGCUUCCUGUCCAGUGGUCCUUCCUGCAUGCACUGCCCCCAGCCCACUCCUCAGCGGCUGAGCCCCUCUUUUUGAGGACACACAUCCUAAAGCACCUGUCACUCAGGGCCGCCCAUGAAAAGCUUCUGACCCCAGCUGUUUCCUUUGGGUCCUUUGAGCUGCCUUCCCUGCAACAGAGAGACACAUGCUAGACUUUUAAAUCCUCUGCUUUCAGAAUCAUCCAGAAUCACAGAUUUUAGGAAAAAUUGGGUGACUGGAAGCAAGCCAUGCAGAGCUGAAUGUUCUGGAUGCUGCCAGCCCUCCCAUGAAGCCAGCUUCCCAGCCCUCACCUCCUCCCCAUGGGCCCCAAACCACCUCACGUAGUUACAUCACUGAUCAACAACAGACACAAUUCUCCUUGGUCAUGAAGAUGAGGGUCUUUCUGGACCCCAAGAUCUCUCAGAGCAACAGUGGAAACAGAAGUGAGAGUUCUGAGGCCAGAGGAGUUGAGUUCCCUAGUUAGGGAGAGCUUGUACCUGGGGCACAGGUCAGGGAAGUUAAGCUCCAUGCCAAGGUCCCCUAACCAGGGGCCACAGUGGGCCUGAGCCCAAGACAUCUGCCCAAGCAGGACAGACGCAGGGCGGCCCACAGGGAGGAGGUCCUGCUGUGCAUCCUUCAGAGCCUUCAGGGUAUUGGGCUUUAUUCUAUAAAGAGGAGUGGUCAGGGGUAUUAUUGUCACAGGCACCGUGAUCAUUCUUACUGCACUUGCAAAGCAGCUGAUCUUGUCUAUUCUCAUGAGUCCUAGGCAGUGAGAUUUUCUUUUUAACCAAAUGUUUAUACAUUGUUCCUCUAGACAAGGGUAAAUAUUACAGAUUCUGUAUGCUUAUUUUUAAAUGUACACAUCCUGUUUGUGACCUUUAAGGAAGACUCUCUGGGAAAGGUAUCGAUUUCCCAAUCUAAGGUGACUUCCUGAGUUGUCAGUGACCACAGUGAGAGCCAAAGCCACAGGCACAGAUGUACUUGUUGCCAGGAGACUUGCGGCUUAUUUUUAACAUAAUUUUUAUUGCUUUAUUCCCGUAAGUACCUGAGUAGCUAAAAGAGAAUUCAAAUAGAUUAUGUCCACUUUUAGCCCCCUUUCCCCCAUUUUAGUAAUUAUCUCCUCCUUGUUUACACAGAUAAACUUACACUUUUAUUGGAAAAUAGGAGAGACCUUCACAUGAACAAGAAGAGGUUGUUCCUCCCGUAUCGAAGCCCAUCUCACCAGUCUCUGUCGUGUCUCCAGACCACGUGAGCGACAGCACCGUCUCUGCCCGGAUCUCAGACAACAGCCUGGCACCAGUGGCUGACUUCAGUUAUCCUGCAGAAUCCUCCUCCUGCCUGGACAACUCUGCAGCUAAGCACAAGCUCCAGGUCAAGCCCCGCAACCAGCGGUCGAGUAAGAUGAGGCGGCUCUCAUCGCGCGCUCAGUCUGAAUCCCUGAGCGACCUGACGUGCACCCCAGAGGAGGAGGAAAACGAGGAGAAGCCACUUUUGGAAGUCAGCCCAGAAGAGCGCCCCAGCUCUGGGCAGCAGGACGUGGCGCCAGACAGAGGCCCUGAGCCUGGGCCACCGGCGCCCUUGCCGCCACCCGGAGGGGCCCGUGCCAGACGCGCCCGCCUGCAGCACUCCUCCGCGCUCACGGCCAGCGUGGAGGAGGGGGGCGUCCCCGGGGAGGACCCCUCAAGCCGCCCGGCCACCCCGGAGCUCGCCGAGCCCGAGUCGGCCCCCACUCUCCGCGUGGAGCCCCCGUCCCCGCCGGAGGGCCCCCCGAAUCCCGGUCCCGACGGCGGAAAGCAGGAUGGGGAGGCGCCCCCCGCAGGCCCGUGUGCCCCGGCCACGGACAAGGCGGAGGAGGUGGUCUGUGCUCCCGAAGACGUCGCGAGCCCGUUUCCCACCGCCAUCCCUGAGGGGGACACGACUCCCCCCGAGACUGACCCCGCCGCCACCUCAGAGGCGCCCUCUGCUCGCGACGGGCCAGAACGCAGUGUCCCGAAGGAAGCGGAGCCGACGCCGCCCGUGCUCCCGGAUGAGGAGAAGGGGCCCCCAGGGCCGGCGCCUGAGCCCGAGAGAGAAGCGGAGACGGAGCCCGAGAGAGGAGCGGGGACCGAGCCCGAGAGAAUUGGGACCGAGCCCUCCACGGCGCCCGCCCCGAGCCCGCCGGCGCCCAAGAGCUGCCUGAAACACCGGCCCGCGGCCGCCAGCGAGGGCCCCGCCGCGUCCCCGCCGCUUGCCGCUGCGGAGUCUCCCCCGGUGGAGCCCGGCCCCGGUUCCCUCGACGCAGAGGCCGCCGCCCCGGAGCGCCCCAAGGCCGAGCGAGCCGAGGCGCCACCGGCGGGCGCCGAGAGGGCGGCGCCAGAGCGGAAGGCGGAGAGGGGCGGUGCCGAGCUGCGAGGCGCGAAGAAGUUCUCGGUGUCCUCGUGCCGAGCGCGGCCUCGUCCGGGCGUCUCCCGCCCGCUGGAACGGGCCAGCGGCCGCCUGCCCCUCGCGAGGAGCGGCCCGGUCUGGAGGAGCGAGGCGGCUCUUGACGACCUCCAGGGUCUCCCCGAGCCCCAGCACGCGAAACCUGGCCCUCGGAAGCUGGCGGAGCGCGGCCCUCAGGACUCGGGGGACAGGGCGGCCAGCCCGGCCGGGCCGCGCAAGAGCCCUCAGGAGGCGGCCGCCGCGCCCGGCACGAGAGAGCCCUGCCCAGCCGCCCAGGAGCCGGCCCCGAGUGAGGACAGAAACCCCUUCCCCGUCAAGCUCCGGUCCACCUCCCUCUCGCUCAAAUACAGGGAUGGCGCCUCUCAGGAGGUGAAGGGUGUGAAGAGGUACAGUGCCGAGGUCCGGUUAGAAAGGUCGCUGACCGUGCUCCCGAAGGAGGAGAAGUGUCCCCUCGGGACGGCCCCCGCCCUUCGAGGCACCAGGGCCCCCAGCGACCAAGGAAAGGGGAAGGCCCGGCCCCCCGAGCCGCUCAGCUCCAAGCCGCCCCUGCCCCGGAAGCCGCUUCUGCAGAGCUUCACGCUCCCGCACCAGCCCGCGCCCCCCGACGCCGGCCCGGGAGAGCGGGAACCCAGGAAGGAGCCCAGGACGGCGGAGAAAAGGCCGCUGCGCAGGGGAGCUGAAAAGAGUCUGCCGCCUGCAGCAACAGGGCCUGGAGCUGAUGGGCAGCCUGCGCCACCCUGGAUCACCGUCACUCGGCAGAAGCGGAGGGGGACCUUGGACCAGCCACCCAACCAGGAAGACAAGCCUGGGGCACGGACCCUGAAGUCUGAACCAGGAAAGCAAGCCAAGGUGCCCGAGAGAGGCCAGGAGCCUGUGAAGCAAGCUGACUUUGUUCGCAGCAAGUCUUUCCUGAUAACCCCUGUGAAGCCCGCUGUGGACCGGAAGCAGGGGGCAAAGCUCAACUUCAAGGAGGGGCUGCAAAGAGGAAUCUCAUUGUCCCAUCAGAACUUGGCAGCUCAGUCUGCAGUGAUGAUGGAGAAGGAACUGCAUCAGCUGAAGAGAGCCAGUUAUGCCAGUACAGAUCAGCCAUCCUGGAUGGAACUUGCCAGAAAGAAAUCUCAAGCUUGGAGUGACAUGCCCCAGAUUAUAAAAUAGGUGGGCAGUGUGCUGAUAAAGCAUGUCCACUACCCUGACAAGCCACUUAGUUAAAAACUGCCAGUGUAUUGUGGCAAACAAACUGUGAAACUUAAAGAUUGAUUUUAUCAUCAAGUUAUGACGAACUUGGGGAAGAGGAAGGAACCAGGCAAAACAAAGAGGAUAAACACACAGCCAUACUCCUGGGCCAGAGGGCCCAGAAACAAGAACAACAUUGAAAAAGUCCAGGAACCAGUUCCUGUGCCCAAAGGUACGAAUGUGUCUUUUCGAAUUCCCUUGAUAAAGAAGCCUCAGACAAGGAAGAAAAUAGAAAUGAAAUUGGACACAUAAAUAGGACACCCAGCAAAGGCCAGAAGAGAAGCCCUUCUAGGAGAAGGGACAUCUGUGCUUCCAGCUGAGAUCAGCCCAUGUCUCUGGUCGCUCUCUUGCCUGUGGAUCCUGUCUUCUUUCAUGUUUACUACGAGGCAUGACAUUCAUGGCAAAACAGGGAUGCCGUUUCCAAGAGCAGCUAUAAAACAAUCUGUUUUCCUAAAGACAGCCACUCUGAGAAGGAGAUGAAGGAACACGGCAGGGUUCAUCAAUUCAUAGACUGUUUCCAAAAAUAAUUUUUAAACUUUUCCACUAGGCAUCUGUGUCUUUAACCACUGCACAAUGCAUUGCCUGUUUAAUAAAAGGUUUCAAACAUG